GGUUUCUCUCCGCAAGCGCGCGAUGCAGCGGGCGGCGGCGCUGGUCCGGCGGGGCUGUGGUCCCCGGACCCCCAGCUCCUGGGGCCGCAGCCAGAGCAGCGCGGCCGCCGAGGCCUCGGCGGUGCUCAAGGUGCGGCCCGAGCGCAGCCGGCGCGAGCGCAUCCUCACGCUGGAGUCCAUGAACCCGCAGGUGAAGGCGGUGGAGUACGCCGUGCGGGGACCCAUCGUGCUCAAGGCCGGCGAGAUCGAGCUCGAGCUGCAGCGGGUGAGCGCGCGCUGGGCCCCGGGGAGGCUGGGGCCGCUGAGCAAGGGAAAAACCGCAGCAGCCCCAGCUGGGGUCCUUCCCACGACGUCCACCCCCAUGGCCAGCUCCUCAGUCAGCCAAGCCUGGCUAAAACGAGAGAAUGCCCCCUCCCGCCCGUUCACUUACUGGUGCCCAGCACCGGGCACUCAGUGAGGCCUUGCAAUACGGUUCACUUGUUGAAUUGAAUUCGUCAAUUGUUGAGCGGGCCGUGCUGCCAGGCACCGCACGUUGUGUGUCUGCCCUACUCUCGUGGAACCAAGGUCCAGUGGAGAGAGGAACAUAAGCGAAUGAAGAAAGAAGCAAUAGAGUCUCAGUGAUAAGUUCUUGGAAAAAAGGUCUUUGCCAAUCCUGAUUCCCGGAAGAGAGUCGGCAGAAUUCCUUCCUUUAGGCCCCUCUGGAGCCUUGGCCGACCAGCCACUUCUGUGGUCUGGGGACAGUCACCGAGGUGGGGAACCAGAGAGUUGGGCCUGUCGGGCUUUGGGUAUCAAAAAGCCAUUCACAGAGGUCAUCCGAGCCAACAUCGGGGACGCCCAGGCUAUGGGGCAGCAGCCAAUCACCUUCCUCCGGCAGGUGAUGGCACUAUGCACCUACCCAAACCUGCUGGACAGCCCCAGCUUCCCAGAAGAUGCUAAGAAACGUGCCCGGCGGAUCCUGCAGGCUUGUGGCGGGAACAGCCUGGGUGAGGCCCCAACUUGCCAGGCCCCUAGGCGUGAAAUGAAUGAGUGUUCCCAGGCGGCCCCAGCCUCAAGCGGAGGGUCCUGCAUGCGAAUGGGGUCCUACAGUGCUAGCCAGGGUGUCAACUGCAUCCGUGAAGAUGUGGCUGCCUACAUCACCAGGAGGGAUGGCGGUGUGCCUGCGGACCCCGACAACAUCUACCUGACCACGGGAGCUAGUGACGGCAUUUCUACGAUCCUGAAGAUCCUCGUCUCCGGGGGCGGCAAGUCACGGACAGGUGUGAUGAUCCCCAUCCCACAAUAUCCCCUCUAUUCAGCUGUCAUCUCUGAGCUCGACGCCAUCCAGGUGAAUUACUACCUGGACGAGGAGAACUGCUGGGCGCUGAAUGUGAAUGAGCUCCGGCGGGCGGUGCAGGAGGCCAAAGACCACUGUGAUCCUAAGGUGCUCUGCAUAAUCAACCCUGGGAACCCCACAGGCCAGGUACAAAGCAGAAAGUGCAUAGAAGAUGUGAUCCACUUUGCCUGGGAAGAGAAGCUCUUUCUCCUGGCUGAUGAGGUGUACCAGGACAACGUGUACUCUCCAGAUUGCAGAUUCCACUCCUUCAAGAAGGUGCUGUACGAGAUGGGGCCCGAGUACUCCAGCAACGUGGAGCUCGCCUCCUUCCACUCCACCUCCAAGGGCUACAUGGGCGAGUGUGGUUACAGAGGAGGCUACAUGGAGGUGAUCAACCUGCACCCUGAGAUCAAGGGCCAGCUGGUGAAGCUGCUGUCGGUGCGCCUGUGCCCCCCAGUGUCUGGGCAGGCCGCCAUGGACAUUGUCGUGAACCCCCCGGUGGCAGGAGAGGAGUCCUUUGAGCAAUUCAGCCGAGAGAAGGAGUCGGUCCUGGGUAAUCUGGCCAAAAAAGCAAAGCUGACGGAAGACCUGUUUAACCAAGUCCCAGGAAUUCACUGCAACCCCUUGCAGGGGGCCAUGUACGCCUUCCCUCGGAUCUUCAUUCCUGCCAAAGCUGUGGAGGCUGCUCAGGCCCAUCAAAUGGCUCCAGACAUGUUCUACUGCAUGAAGCUCCUGGAGGAGACUGGCAUCUGUGUCGUGCCCGGCAGUGGCUUUGGGCAGAGGGAAGGCACUUACCACUUCAGGAUGACUAUCCUCCCUCCAGUGGAGAAGCUGAAAACGGUGCUGCAGAAGGUGAAAGACUUCCACAUCAACUUCCUGGAGAAGUACGCGUGAGGACGCCUGAGCCCCAGCGGGAGACCUGUCCUUGGCUCUUCCUCCCAAUGCCCGUCAGGCUGAACUCGCCUCCCCCGUGACUCUGCCUCGGGCCUCGCAGAGGCCGCUGGUCACUUCGUCAUCAUUUUGCCCCUGGAGACGUCUUUCUUUGUGCCUUGAUGUUGAGAGCGCCUCUCUUUUGAGCAAACAAGCAUUCUAUAUGCAACCAGAGUAGAGGGGACCUGCUCAGCAGGUGUGACCAGGGUUCUCUGAAUCUGUUAUUGUUUUUGCUUCUGGAAAGUUCAUUUGGGGUUUACAACAACUAGGAUGUGUUGGGUGAGAUGUUUCAGAUCUGGAGAAAUGAGCAGGUGUCGGGAAAUGUGUGACUUAACCGUGGUGAGGGCUGGAAAUCCAAACUCACCACCAUGAUCUGUGAAAUAAAGCCCUUAGCGGUGUGAAGCAUCCGGUCCUUUGAACAGAAGGGCCUGGAAGGCCCCUGGGGCUGAGAAAGGGUCCGCCCGGUGGCCUGGAGGCAGGCGCCGGGAGCGCAGUAGCACGUGGACUGGGCAGGAUGUUGCACUAGCUUGGGGUAGAUGCUGGGGGCUGCGGCCACGGUCAGAGGGCCCCACUGUGAGGCGUGGGUGUGAGCCAGGCUGCAGGAGGAACUGGGCCUCCGCUUCCCAGCAACGCAGCCAGGCCUGAGAAUUCUGUGCGCCCGGCGGGCUUUGGGAAUGAGGGGUUCCCUUGAACAUGCGUAGGCUGGAACCCCGUCUGAGAGGUCUCCCUGAAUUUCAGUGACACAUAGUGCAGCCCGGCAGUGUCCCACUUCCGUGGAGAGAGCCGCUGGAAUGGUGUGGACCCAUCCCGCGGGUGACCGGUGCCUGUUCUCCCCUGACCGAGCCUGUGAGCACAUCGCCCCCUGCUGGCGACAGCGGGGAAAUGAGGGCUGAAAAUAUCCUCCCCACAAGGGCAAUCCCCGGGACCUGCCGAGCAGCCAAGGCCCUGUCCUUUCUUGAAUGGUGGCGAGCUGAAUCUGGUCGGUUUCCUAGCUUUUAGGUGGUAAAAGUGCCUGGCAGCUUGGCUGCCGUGGAGGAGUCAGUCGUGGUUGGAGGUUCAUUGCCGUGCUUUCAUGCAGAGUGUUUUGCCUUCAUGUUAGCUUCCGGCUCCCCUCCCAGGCUGCAGACUCUGACCUGUGGCAUCAGGCUUCUCCCAGUACAGGAGGGUGCCAUCCCCCAGCAUGCGGCUUCUCUGCCAUUAGCAGCCCUGGGCGGGCCGACCACACUCGAGGCUGCGGUGCUACGGGCUUAGCCCUCGCCUCCCUCACUGGGAGCUUCCCCAUCCUCCCUGCCUUCCCCAGUGGGAAGUUAGGGAAGCUCAGGAGCCUGGGACCCCGCAUGUCCCAAAAUGGGAUUGGAGAAGCUGGAGAGAAAGCAGAAGAGGCCGAGGAGUGAGGCAGCAGCCUCUAUGCUGUGAUUUCCACACCGGGUCCGUGCAGAGGAAACAGAAACUCCCAACUGUCCUUACCCACCGACAUCACAGCCCCUAUGAAGAAAGUAGCCACAAUCUCAAAUAACAAAAGGGAAUGUUCUAAAACUUUUUCUUCCUUAAAAAAUGGAGAAAAUUGCACUUGUGCUUGCUGUGUGGUAUAUAAACCAGGAUUAGUCCCAGGGUCGUGAGGUUUCUGGUGAAAAGGUUAAAUCGUAGAAGCUAGUAUAUUUUUUAUAUUUUUGUAACAAUUGCUUUUUUCAUGGGGGAGGCGGGGUUAGUAUUUAUAGUCCUAACAAGUCCAGUAAUUUUUUAUAAAUCUUCAGAUUAUAAACAGCCCCUAAAAACUUUACAACGUUUACACAGUUUUUUAAAAAGAGACUGUAUACACUUGAUUUGCUUUCAAAAUAAAUAAGGUCAGCUAGUCUAGGAGGUUAACGUCGGGUAGGAAUGCUGAUCAUGAUAGGUUUGGUUUUCUACAGAUUCUGUUCCGGUGCCUUUCCUAUCCAGGCACCACCUGAGAAAGUUGUCAUUUGAGGUCGCACUUGGAAGUUACAUCUGUGAAGUUUCUGUCAUUCGUCCAGAUCUGUGUGUGUAGCAUGUGCUGAGGAAGCACGUGCUGGGCUGUGCCUCAGACAGUGCAUCACCGGGCACCCAGAGGCUUGCCUGGCUAUUCCUGUUCUGGUGUGUGUGGAGUGUUGGGGAGGAACAGAUGCAGAUCAACCUGUGGCUGUUUUCCCGUCUAGGUUCUCACAGGUAUCUCCUGACAGAGGUACUUAACAAUGGCUCUGCUGGAAAUUUCUAUAAAUAAAAUGUCCAAAAUGGUGA